GAGCUUGUUUGCCAGGGACACUGCAAGUAGGAAGUGUCUACAGGUCGAUGACAGGCCUAAUCUCUAUGACAGGGUCUAGACUUUCCUCAGGGUCCAGGGGCGCACCUCAGGGUGAACUGGAAAACUCGACCGCACUUUAGUGCCAGGACCAUGGCCAACCUGGAGCGCACCUUCAUCGCCAUCAAGCCGGACGGCGUGCAGCGCGGCCUGGUGGGCGAGAUCAUCAAGCGCUUCGAGCAGAAGGGAUUCCGCCUCGUGGCCAUGAAGUUCCUCCGGGCCUCUGAAGAACACCUGAAGCAGCACUACAUUGACCUGAAAGACCGACCAUUCUUCCCUGGGCUGGUGAAGUACAUGAACUCAGGGCCGGUUGUGGCCAUGGUCUGGGAGGGGCUGAACGUGGUGAAGACAGGCCGAGUGAUGCUUGGGGAGACCAAUCCAGCAGAUUCAAAGCCAGGCACCAUUCGUGGGGACUUCUGCAUUCAGGUUGGCAGGAACAUCAUUCAUGGCAGUGAUUCAGUAAAAAGUGCUGAAAAAGAAAUCAGCCUAUGGUUUAAGCCUGAAGAACUGGUUGACUACAAGUCUUGUGCUCAUGACUGGGUCUAUGAAUAAGAGGUGGACACAACAGCAGUCUCCUUCAGCACGGCGUGGUGUGUCCCUGGACACAGCUCUUCAUUCCAUUGACUUAGAGGCAACAGGAUUGAUCAUUCUUUUAUAGAGCAUAUUUGCCAAUAAAGCUUUUGGAAGCCGGA